ACACAUCUAUACCAUUUUUAAAAAUUUAUUUUUUCUGGCAAUAAAAUACUUUAUUGGUACUGUUUAAUAAACGUCAAAAACAUAGUAACAUUUCCAUUGGUUAGCUUCCAUCUUUAAACUAAAAGCUAGUUUAAAAACAAUAGGAGGAAAAGUAAACUCAUUUGAUUCUCUCGAAAAACAAGCUGUAACUUACCUUUGCAAAUAAUUACGUUAUCUCACUUUAAAUAUUAUAAUUCACUGGUCUUUGUAAUACACAAUUGUAUUAAUAUAUAAAAGGAGACAGUGGCCUGAUUUUGCAGAGAAUAUUUCACACAUCUUUAAAAAAAUCCCUAAACACUACCACAACUCAAAACUUGUAAGAAUAAUUAGGUAAGAGUUAUUAUAAUAUUGAAUUAAUAUAGCACCUAGAAAUUUGAAAUUUGUAAUAUUUCAGAUGAUAUGAUUUACUGAGAAAAAGAGUAAUGAUUUUUCUUCAGUGAAUUUUCAGGGGUUUACAUACUAAUAGAAUUCAACAUAGGUCUCUUUUAAAAGCUGAAGGUUAAAAAAUUUAUGCAUGCUAGGAAUUGACCUGAUGGUAACAGAUCCAUGUGUGACAAAUAAUCACACAUAGUGCAGUCCUAUCUGAAUAUAAUUUCUUCUUCACUUUGUCUCAUUAAUUUAUACCUCAAAACAUUCUAUAUGCAAGUGAUAUAUUUCUCUAAAACAUUCCAUAUUUCAGAUUUCCAUUCAGACUAUCUUCCCCUCCUCCUCUCUUUUCUCAAAUCAGAGUGACCUUGUGGUAUACCAUUUGCUUUUUCUCCCCACAAUGAAACUCUUUUUCAACUCAAAGUAUUAUAGUAAUGCAAAUACAAAUGUAGCAUAUAUUAAUAUAUUAGAAAAAAGGAUAGCAAAUACAUAUGGGUCCAUGCCAAAUGAGAAAAUCGAAAGCAAAAACAAAACCUUGCUAUGCUCAUCUAUUCUGAACCACCAUGGGAAGACCCUGAUGUAGCUGGCGCACAUAAACUAAUGUUCCCAGACACAGCUAGGAUCCUGUACUCCAACAUAAUUAAAUGCUCUGUUAAAAAGGUUUCCGUGUUCUUUUCUGUUUGUGCAAAAUAGUCUAUAGCAACUCUGACUACUAAUCCUGAGCAUGAUGAUAAUGUAAUAGCAUUAUAUUUUUAAUCAAGCCAUAGAUUCUAACCUGUUUUCUACUAUUACCCAUUUGCUUAAAAACAGACUUUCAGGAGGCUAAGCAACAGUAAGUUAAGGAGUUUUUAUUUCUACCUUUCUCUUGAUUGAUUGAUUGAGGAUUUCAGAUGUGUCAAAUAAUUAUCCUCUGCUUCAGUGGAAAAGGAUUCUUCAAGCUAUCAAAUCAAGCACGCUGACUCAGGGGUGGGCAGAUGAAGAUACCUGUCCACACACUAUGCUCAUAGCACUCCAUCUCCUCUGUAAGAAUGUGCUGCUCUUCACCCAACAGCAGCCCAGCACAUUCCAUCCGCUCCACCUAGAUGCAAUCAGGACACCAUGCAAUCCCACACACAAUCAGAACAUGGGCACCAGGUAGAACUAACUCAAAACAACUUUUGGGACAAAUACGAGAUUUUAAUUUGUCAAUUAUUCCAUAGUGCAGUAUUUUCACAAAACAGAGACUUUGUGUUGAAACAUUUGUUUUUUUCAUCUCUCAUCAAGUUGAACUGCUAAAGUAAUGUCAGAAAGGAAAAAUAAACAUGUCUUCUCCAAAAGAGGCACUGCAUCCGGAAGUGGAAUUAAGGCUAAAUAAAUAGUGCUGGUUUGCGGUUCACACAGUAACGCAUUAAUUAUGAUUUCAACCAACAGCUUCGCUGUUUGUCCUGUAUGCCUGUUUAUGAAGAUGCGUCUCUAUUUCCUCCCUGAAGACCAGCAUUCCCAGGUGGGAGCGAGAGGCCUCAUUUAUGGCUUUAGACUGGAUGCACAUGCGGUACUGCUCGGGGGUCAGCUCAUCAGCACAGCGUUUUUCAGGCCAGAGGUGGAAAAGACCAGUAACCGGAGUCCAAAUCACAAUGAGGUCACCAUGCAGUCACCCUGGGUUAAAUGUGGUGUGCAGGUCUGUGUUGGAGUGGAUAUACAGCUUUCUGCUGGACCCUGCUGACACUGGCAAAAGUGAAGCACCUUGCCCCAUCUUGUUGCCAAUGGAUGGAAGUGAAAGUUUAGUUCCCCACUCAGCCUUGCAGAUACCUCCCUGGCAAAAGCAUAGAACUGACUCACAUCACUUUGUUGCUGCUGGGUGAGAUUAUGUUUGGAGGCCAUGAUUAAGUACCUCACACUGUGGAAGAAAGAGGAGCAGGAGGAGCCCUAUGUCAGCCUCACCCGAAAGAAGAUGCUAAUAGAUGGCGAGGAGGUGCUGAUAGAAUGGGAGGUGGGCCACUCCAUCCGGACCCUGGCUAUGCACCGCAAUGCCUACAAACGUAUGUCACAGAUCCAAGCCUUCCUGGGCUCAGUGCCCCAGCUGACCUAUCAGCUCUAUGUGAGCCUGAUCUCUGCAGAGGUUCCCCUGGGUAGAGUUGUGCUAAUGGUAUUUUCCCUGGUAUCUGUCACCUAUGGGGCCACCCUUUGCAAUAUGUUGGCUAUCCAGAUCAAGUACGAUGACUACAAGAUUCGCCUUGGGCCACUAGAAGUCCUCUGCAUCACCAUCUGGCGGACAUUGGAGAUCACUUCCCGCCUCCUGAUUCUGGUGCUCUUCUCAGCCACUUUGAAAUUGAAGGCUGUGCCCUUCCUAGUGCUCAACUUCCUGAUCAUCCUCUUUGAGCCCUGGAUUAAGUUCUGGAGAAGUGGUGCCCAGAUGCCCAAUAACAUUGAGAAAAACUUCAGCCGGGUCGGCACUCUGGUGGUCCUGAUUUCAGUCACCAUCCUCUAUGCUGGCAUCAACUUCUCUUGCUGGUCAGCUUUGCAGUUGAGGUUGGCAGACAGAGAUCUCGUCGACAAAGGGCAGAACUGGGGACAUAUGGGCCUGCACUAUAGUGUGAGGUUGGUAGAGAAUGUGAUCAUGGUCUUGGUUUUUAAGUUCUUUGGAGUGAAAGUGUUACUGAAUUACUGUCAUUCCUUGAUUGCCUUGCAGCUCAUUAUUGCUUAUCUGAUUUCCAUUGGCUUCAUGCUCCUUUUCUUCCAGUACUUGCAUCCAUUGCGCUCACUCUUCACCCAUAAUGUAGUAGACUACCUCCAUUGUGUCUGCUGUCACCAGCACCCUCGGACCAGGGUUGAGAACUCAGAGCCACCCUUUGAGACUGAAGCAAGGCAAAGUGUUGUCUGAUUCUAUUUUCUGGGUAUUUUAGGAAGAGUUGGGAGUUGCCAAGAGUAACCAUGAAAUUGAACGAAAGGAUGAGGUUCAUGGGUGAGAUACCCAUCAGUACAUUUUCUUGACUUUUCUGUUAAGCCUAUCAGAAGAAAGAGCAACUCCCAAAUAGGUUUUAUUUUCUUAAGAGUUACCACUAUGUUUGGAAACAGGGGGUAUCGACUAUAUAGUUGAAAGGGUCAGAAAUACCAUUCACACCCUUCUUACCCAAGUCAAUUGGAAUAACUUGUCUUCAAACACUUUAGGCUCUCUAAAGUGACCUUCUAGCUCUGCUCAUUUGCUUGAUGCAUUUCUGAGCUUUCCUGGGCUGAGCUGAAGGCCCAGAAUCCCGCUAGAAUAUAUCCUGACUGAUCAGAGGAUAUGACAGCUUACCAGCUAAGAGUACCUCCCAGGAAACAGUCUGACUAAUGUGGAACCUGCAACUGUCAGUGUGGCUGGGGUCUUUUUAAUUCCAGUGAGAAGCUCUGGCUGAGAAGAAAAUCACCACUAUUAAAAAAGCUGCUCCCCAAGCAGAUUAGCUCUCUGUUAGGAUUUUACUAGUGGCCAUUCAGCAAGGACCUCUCUUUACAGUGGCACUUCAUAGGCACACUCUAAGGAGAAAGUGCAGAGUAGAAUUCCUUCAGGGCAUAAGCCAAAAUGACUCUUUUUCUCAGGGACCUGCAUGGGCCUCCAGCUUGUCUAUUGGAAUUGUUAAGUGAAGCCUCUCACUUAGUGCCUCAUUAGCAGAGAUUUCCUCCAACCCAGCUUUUCUGUGCUCUUGGUAUUUUACUACUUGAUGUGGACCUCAGAGAAGCUGAACUGUAAUUGAAAAUGUUUCCGAUGUGUGGAAGAAAUGAAGACUGCUUUGUGUC